AUUCACUCCCCUUUCCCAGCCCCGGGAGGGCGCAGCGCCCGGGUGGGGAGCCCGAGCCAGCCCAGGCCGGCUCUGGCCUCCUGACCCAGACAGCGCAGGGCGCGAGGGAUCGCGCGGCCGAGCCCGGGUCGCGCCGCUCCCAGCAUCGGGGCCGCUAGCCAAGAGUUCGAGGCCUUCCCGAUCCGGAUGUGAUGAAAAAGAGCAACAGAGGGAGAAGUGUUUCAGGAUUGUAGGAGUGGAAGAGGGGAAAGAGAGGCAGAGAGGGGGAAGGCCCCCUCGCAGGGGAGCCGGCUGGAGUGAGCUGGCUGGAAAGAGGGGGCGGAGUGCGCGGAGUCAGAGCCGCCACCGCUGCCGCAGUUGCCGCCACUGCGGCGUCUGGGCUGAGCCGGAGGGAGGCGGGAGGACGCGCAGGGGCGGCCGCCGCCGUCGUCAGGCCACCGGGGCGAAAAUGCGGCCGCUGCCGGAGGCUCGCUAACUUUCCGGGGCGGAAGAGGAGGAGGAGGAGGAGGAAGGGGCUUGGAGCGACUACGGGGGGAUGCGGAGAAGCAGUCAGUUCCCUGCACCCAGCACCUCACAGCCCUUCCUCCGUGCGCCCUGCCGGGCGGCGAGCUAGGCGGCAGCGGCGCGGCGCGGGCUCGGCGGAGCGGCCCAUGUCCGGCGCGGGCGAAGCCCUCGCUCCCGGGCCCGUGGGGCCGCAGCGCGUGGCCGAGGCGGGCGGCGGCCAGCUGGGCUCCACAGCCCAGGGAAAAUGUGAUAAAGACAAUACUGAGAAAGAUAUAACUCAAGCUACCAAUAGCCACUUCACACAUGGAGAGAUGCAAGACCAGUCCAUUUGGGGAAAUCCUUCGGAUGGUGAACUCAUUAGAACCCAACCUCAGCGCUUGCCUCAGCUUCAGACUUCAGCCCAGGUGCCAAGUGGUGAGGAAAUAGGCAAGAUAAAGAACGGCCACACAGGUCUGAGCAAUGGAAAUGGAAUUCACCACGGGGCCAAACACGGAUCCGCAGAUAAUCGCAAACUUUCAGCACCUGUUUCUCAAAAAAUGCAUAGAAAAAUUCAGUCCAGCUUGUCUGUAAACAGCGAUAUCAGUAAGAAGAGCAAAGUAAAUGCUGUCUUUUCCCAAAAGACAGGCUCUUCACCUGAAGAUUGUUGUGUCCACUGUAUCCUGGCUUGCUUGUUCUGCGAAUUCCUGACCCUUUGCAACAUUGUCCUGGGACAAGCGUCAUGUGGCAUCUGCACCUCAGAAGCCUGCUGCUGUUGCUGUGGUGACGAGAUGGGGGAUGAUUGUAACUGCCCUUGUGAUAUGGACUGUGGCAUCAUGGAUGCCUGUUGUGAAUCAUCAGACUGCUUGGAAAUCUGUAUGGAAUGCUGUGGAAUUUGUUUUCCUUCAUAAAUAUUUAUCUUUUGUUUGUGUUAAAACUGGAGAGUGUUUAAAAAUUUCCUUUUGGGGGGAAGAAAAGCACAUUGUAAGAUUCUCAUGAAACAACAUGGAAUUUGCACUGUUAACUCAUUAUUGUAAGUAAUCUCUGAAAGCCUUUUUACUUUAACCAAAUCUACAUGGUUUAAUAUGUGAAAUUUUAACUACUUUAACUAGUUUUAUAAAUUUCUUAAUAUGUUACAAUAACUUAGGGACAUUUUGACACCCCCCUUCCCAAAUGUUAAAUGCCUUCUCCUUUUUACCGAUAUUUCUGUUUCUUUUAACCGUUCUCAGGAGCACUUUGCUCCAAAUAUAUUAUUUUUCAGUGUGUAUUUAAACGAGGCAGUUUAUUUUGAUAUGUAUCUAUUCAUGAUUGAAAGGAAGCAGUCUUGGCCAGGCACGGUGGCUUACACCUGUAACCCUGGCAUUUUGGGAGGCCAAGGUGGGCAGAUUGCCUGAGCUCAGGAGUUCGAGACCAGCCAGGGCAACAUGGUGAAACCCCAUCUCUACUAAAAUACAAAAAGUUAGCUGGGCUUGGCGGUGUGCGCCUGUAGUCCCAGCUACUCAGGAGGCUGAGGCAGGAGAAUUGCUUGAACCCGAGAGGCGGAAGUUGCAGUGAGCCGAGAUUGUGCCACUGAACUCCAACCUGCACUCCAGCCUGGGCAACAGAGCGAGACUCCAUCUCUAAAUAAAUAAAUAAAUAAAUAAAUAAAUAAAUAAAUAAAUAAACAAACCAGUCUUUAUUUUAAAAGAAACUUUAGGAAACAAACCCACAUAAUAGUUGGGAACCAGUGUUGAUCUCUCUCCCUUACCUUCUCCACUUGUUCAACAGACUCUGAAUGCCGACUGUGUGGACUCUCUUCCUCAGACUGUGGGGACAGAUACAAUUCCACUCCUGUCCACAGGAACAUGAGAUUUAGCAGACUAAGGAGAUCUGUAAAGAAUGAACCAUACCACAAGGCAUACUGAAGUGAGGAUUAUAAGAGAAAUAAACUCAAAAUGCUGUUGGAAUAUGCAGAGAAUUGCUACCAGAAUAUUCAGUAAGGUUUCAGGGAGAAUGUGGCAUUUGAGGACUCUCUUAGAAUGAGUGAUUCACCUGCUAUUUAAAUGAAUUAUUUAGAUUUUUGACAAAGAUUUAGGUGGACACCCUAAACUGUGUGUGCCUUUAACCAGUUAAAAGAACAGUGCCUUCAGCAUACUUUUUUAUUAGUUGUAGGAAUACAGCUUUUUGAAAAAGCUAUAAAGUUUAAAUUAACUAAAAAUAUGCAUUUUCUUACACAUAAUUUAAAUGUUAUCAUACUUUUUUGAUGAAAACAUAAUGCCUUAGUAAAAUAGCUCUAUUUAAUAAAGAAGAUUGAGUACUCUGACACAUUUCAUUUAAAUUAGGAAAUUUUUAAUAUUAAAAUCCCAGUGUUCUGAGUUAUUGAAAGGCUUUCUUUUAUUUUGAGAGCUUUAGGUCUUUUUGGGAUGAGAACAUUUUAGUUGUUUAGUUUGUUUCUUAAGCAGUGCUAUUUUUUGUAAACACAGAUAAAUGGAAACCAUUCUUUUCAAUGCAGAAGAAAUCUAGAUAUCCCCUACUGUGACCAAAUUUCUGUAUUACGAUUUUAUGUUAAAUUAAACUAAUAUGGCAGGUUAUAAUGAUCCUUAAGUGUAAAGAAAUCAGUCAAUUACAAGAGUAAUUGUAUAGUUAUUGAGACCUAUAGUGUGUGGCUUAGAUGAAAGGGAGAGUAAAUUUUCAUACCAUGCUCUCUCCUACUCAGUUUGAUCUCUCUAAAAUUGUAGUUUGGUUUGAUUUAAUAUAAUUCUUAGUAGAAAUUUUGAAAGUAUGCUUUGGGAUUAAUAAUUAUUUUUAAUUUUUCUGGCUGAAUAUCAAAUUGAUAGUAACAACAGAAGCAUAAUUUUAGGAAGGCUUUCGCAAACCUAGCCUUUUAAGAGAGGUUUUUAACCUGAAGCAUGAGAAUAUAUCACCUGUGGUUUUUCCUUUGAGAUGAAACGUAGUUUCUAGUUAUAUCAUUACUUAAAGGGCUUAAAAAGAAAAAACUUAGCAAACUUUUGAAUCUUUCUUUUAUUGCUAUUUACACAUACAUACACACAUACAAAACCUUUAAAUUUUGGGAUCUGAAUAUAAUUCUGGUAAACAGCUGUCUUCAUUUUUCUCCUCUAAAGAACUUAAUUCAUUUGUUACAUAAAAUAUAAGGAAAUCUUUAUACUAUUUUACAGUAACCACAAUCUAAAUAUUUACAUAUACCCAAAAUUAACUUAUGCUCAUAUAUUAGGAUGUGAGAAUAUCAUCUGUUUAUGGACACAUGAAACCUCCUAAUGACCUGGAAUUGUUAGAAUAUUUGACUUUUUAUAUGCAAAGUUUUUCAACCAAGUGGUUUGUCUAAUAUUUAAACAUGUACUGGCACAAUUUGUGAUGAAAAUAUUAGCACAUUUGCAAUAAUGUUUCUCCAUAACAGAGAAUGUUAAUGGAUACCAGAAUUUUAUUUUUGUAUUUAUGUUCAUAGUACUUUUCCUCUUGUCUACUCCAGACAGUUAUUCCAUAAAGCAUUUGUAUAAUUAAAAGGAAAACAGAAAAAGGAAAAGUAGGCAAAUGUGAAAAUAGUUUCAAUAUAUCUUAUGAUUUCUUAAUGUAAAAUGUUUUGUUGAAGUAUAUGGCUAUCAUGACUAAGUGCUAGAAUUUAUAGUUACAGGCGGUGUCCUUUUAAAUGUGGAAAGGCUUUUAAAAUAUUUUAAAACUGGACCUGUAUUAUCCUGAAUACACUAUUUUGAAAAUUUUUAAAAAUGACUUCUUUAUUUUGCUUUACCGUAUGUUUAUAUCUAAUUGACAUAUUGACUAAUGUUUGAAAGAAUUCAACCAUAAGUUAAAAUCUGAAGGUUAUCUUUAUCAUGUUUCAUCCCUGUCUGAAGAUUUCCUAGUCUUCUUAUGUAAAUCACAUGACUCAUGUCCGUAAAUGAACUAUGAAAGAUAUCGAUCAGUUUAUGAUCAUUGACAUGUGAUUUCAAAACACAGUGUUCUUUUAAAAAUCUAUAAUAUGUCAAAAUACAAGUUUUUUUUUUUUACAUCGUUUUAGUAAGUUAAUUUCAUUUAUUUACUUUGGAGCUAUAUUUCCACUUAGAAAAACUAAGGUAAUUUUACAAUAUAUGCUGAGAUUAAAAACCAAGGUAAAAAUGAUCAAACAUAUAUGAAAUUGAGUCUUAGAUUUAAUGAAUUUCACUCGAAAAUAAAUGAUCAGAAGAAUUUUCAUCUAAGGCAUAGAGUGGCGAAAUUUUUGUAAAUGCUCGCAGUUAGCAUCUAACUAAAACAAUACAGUAUGACUUUAUUUAGGAGAAGGCUUUUUAUUUAGAAAAUUAUUUUUUCAUUUUUACAGUGUAUCAACUGUAUCCAUUUUCCUCACCUGGAUAGUCAAUGUUAUCUGAGCAGUUCAAGGAGUAACCAAGGCAACCUUAUGUAAUAACUUUCCAUUCUUUAUCCAUACAAACUCUUUCAGUGCCCUAGAUUCUAAUGUUAUAAACGUCAAACAUCACUGCCCAACAUAAAUAAGACUCGAGACUUAUUAACAUAAAUAAGUAUCUUGCCUUCUUGAAUGCUAGUUAAAUGCUUAGAUUUACCUAACUGCCUAAUGAAUCAGGUUAUUUGUUAAUAAGAUUAUUUUUCAAAUUAUUUAAGACCUUUAUGCCCCUUCCAAUUACUUGUGAUUUGUAGGCCUGUAGGAUUGUUGCAUCUAAUCUGACUGGCAACAGAAAAUGUCAUCAAAUACUAUAAUAUCCAUUUUGUUUUCUUUUGCACUAAUACAACAGAACAUAUCAUUUUUGUUUUAAACAAUGGUUAAUAUAUUAAUAGGGUUUGUUCCACACUUACUAUUUAUAGUUUUUAUAAUCAAGCAUUGGGUAUUAAAAGAGAAUCCUUUCAACCCUUCAUCUUCGUAUGCUUAUACAAUAAAUUGCAGUGAGUGUU